AGUCAUAAGCAUAAAUGUUCUAAGAGUGUACAACAGGACUUUGCGUCCGUCAGUGAGGAUAACAAGUCUGUCAUUGGAUAGAUCCUAAGUGAAAUUAGAUAUAAAAGAGAAAUGAAUUGAAUUUACUGGACAACAUUCUUCAGAUCUGCUGGGACAUAUUUUCAUUUUCUGUGAGUACUGGAAUGGAUUGGGACAAGUGAGCAUCUCAACAUCUUUUGUGAAAAAGGAGAACGUGGAUGUCACUGGCUUUCACUUCAUGUUUUAGGUCAGCGCUGCUUUUGGGGUGAAAGAAGACCAUCAGCAAACCUCAGCCUUGCGGCCAGGACUCCCCCGUCUUCUGUCGGAGUCCGCCGGUCCGCAGCCUGCGGCAGGGAGGCCCGGGCACCCGCAGGUGGCGCCCCACGUCCGUGUUUGCGCCCUCAGCCGAGCUCCAGGCGCAGCUGGGAAACCCAGCGCGUCUCCCCGGGUCCUUUGAGCGAGCGCGGACACCGCAAUUUAAUAAAUAAGCGCAAGCGCCAGCCGCUCCACCAGUCCGAGGUCCAGAGGAGCAGACACACAGACCCGGGCCGGAGGCCCCUCUUCUAGCCCUGCGGGAACCGGACAGUUCCCCAACUGGGACUCUGGAACCACAGCUCCUAAAUCAUCAAAUUCUCAAGCUUUUUUUUUCCCUCUCUUCGUCCCAGCCAUCCCAGUCUUCUUCUUCUUUUUUUUUUUUUUAACUUAUUGUUUUUUUCGCUCCUGUCAUUAUGAAAGUGGUCACGCCAUUCAAUAUUAAGACUUGGAGGGAAUUGGGGAAAGAAAAGAAAGAAUCUAAAAGAAGAGAAGCGACCGGUGCUUUUAAGGGUGUCUAAUUUUCAAAAGAGACGUCUGGGAGUAUUUUGCUCUGGGCGUUUGGAGCAACUUCGCGGACAGCGGAGCUCGCCCAGCAUGGAUGUUCCAGGUAACCACCCCCGACCUGCCCUCCCCUCCGCAUGCAAGCGCCUUCUGCGUGGAUUUUAACGAAGACUCUCCCUGGUCCAGAUCGAGGGGUGGAGGAGGUGGAGAGAGAGAAGGGAAAUCAUGUAGGAUCGGGGCUGCGGACAGCGGAUAUUUAUCAAGAGCCAACUUCUCUGUUCUUAGAAAGAAUACUGGAAGAGUUAAUGGGAGGCUGUGGGCGGCGAGGGGGCGGCUUCUCUGCGUGUCUCUGGGCUGGUAUUGAAAUGGCCUGUCUGCUUUCCUGGGAGGAGCGGGGACGGGGCAAAAGUGCAGACGGGCGCGUAAGUUCGCAGAAACCUGCAGGGGCUGCCGCCCCGCUGAGAAAGAGAGAAUCCCCGUGGUCUGGAAACCAGAGCUGGAGAAUAACCCAAGCCUGGGAUUCCGUCGUUGGAAUCGGUCCUUCGCCUAAGAGAGGAAUCCCAGGGGUUUCACCCAAGGGGGCUCGCUAGUGGCUGCAGGGACCUUGGAAGUUCACAGGCGCCUUUCUUCUGAGAACGACCCUGGCCUUGAACGUCAGAGCCGGGGACGAAGGCCCCCGGAGGCUGCUGCGAGCUCCGCGCGUUCCUUCGCGCCCUUCCGCGCCGCUCGCGCCGGCGCCGGCCUCCACCCCCGCGCGCCGCCUCCCACCAGUCCCGAUGCAGGCGCCCGGCCGGGGGCCACUCGGGCUGCGGCUGAUGAUGCCCGGGCGCCGGGGGGCGCUGCGCGAGCCGGGCGGCUGCGGAUCCUGCCUGGGGGUGGCGCUGGCCCUGCUGUUGCUGCUACUGCCCGCCUGCUGCCCCGUGCGGGCGCAGAACGACACGGAGCCCAUCGUGCUGGAGGGCAAGUGCCUGGUGGUGUGCGACUCCAGCCCGUCGGCGGACGGCGCCGUCACCUCCUCCCUAGGCAUCUCCGUGCGCUCCGGCAGCGCCAAGGUGGCCUUCUCCGCCACGCGGAGCACCAACCACGAGCCGUCCGAGAUGAGCAACCGCACCAUGACCAUCUAUUUCGACCAGGUAUUAGUAAAUAUUGGCAACCACUUUGAUCUUGCUUCCAGUAUAUUUGUAGCACCGAGAAAAGGGAUUUAUAGCUUCAGCUUCCACGUGGUCAAAGUGUAUAACAGACAAACCAUCCAGGUCAGUUUAAUGCAGAAUGGCUACCCAGUGAUCUCGGCCUUUGCAGGAGACCAGGAUGUCACCAGAGAAGCUGCUAGCAAUGGCGUGCUGCUGCUCAUGGAAAGGGAAGACAAAGUGCAUCUCAAACUUGAGAGAGGCAACCUCAUGGGGGGCUGGAAAUACUCCACAUUCUCGGGCUUCUUGGUGUUUCCUCUAUAAACACAGAGCCCCCUAGAUGGUGGGGGAAUGGCAAACUGGACCCAGGACUCCGCCCUUUAAAACACCCUGAACUUACUGGAAUUGGACACCUUGUUUCCAACCUCCGUCAGACUGUUGCAGUAGAAGAAUGAUUUCCUUUGAAACCUCCAGUACUUUUGUUUUUGUUUUUUGGAAUACUGACAAUUCCUCGGGAACCUGGCCUCUAAUUAGUUUUAGAUGACAAGGUCUUAAGGAGAAAUGAAAUUAUCGAUUUGAGCAAUUUGUACCUGUGAUUGUAAAGUCAAUAUCGGAUUUUAUUGUUGGGACCAUGGACCUCUUUUGUUUGUAUGUUGUAUUGUCGUCCCAACGGAAGGAGAGCUCCUGACUCCAGGAUGGGCUGCAGGUUGCAGUCAGGGCUUGAAGUAGGAGCCCAGCAAAGAACCACCUGCUGGACAGUCCUUGACAUGUGUUCUGUGUGUGUCUGUAUAGCCUUAAGAAAAAGAAUGGCUUCACUUUCAUUCUGUAUUCUUCCCCCCACCAUGUGGCUGGGAGGACUUGGGAGGGGGAUGGGGACAUUGGGAACCUGUCAAGAAGUGCUUUAUCCAGAGAAGCAAAUUUUGCACGAUUGGACUGCAAUUUUUGUUUUGUAUUGUUUGUGUUUUUUCUUGAAAAGCUUUACUUUUCUUUCCACACUCAGCUCUCCCUCCUCAACCCCACUUUUAUUUUUCUUGCUGGGGUUGAGGAGAGAAAAUAUAGAAUUCCUGGAUAAGACCAAACAAAACAAAACAUUAAAAUACCUGUAUGUUUUGUUUUAGACGAGACCAAACUAAACAAAAAGUAUCUGUUUAUCAAAGUAAAAGUAACACAAUGGACAAUUCUGCUUAUUCUCUCAAAGAGAUUCUAAGAUGCACCUUUAGAACUAUUAAUAGCAACCUGCAUUUUUUUUUAAUUUAUACUUCAGAAUCCUUUAAGAACCUGGUGUUCCUGAGUGGUCCUGAAUCAUAUAAGUUGGUAAUGGAAGCUGUAAUGACCAAGUCCCCUAAACAUACUAUGUCUUUGCCACGUGUGCUGUGACUUCUCUGUGGGUGAUUUAAUUUAUUUGGAUCCACCUCUGAGUGAGCGCACAGUGAUCAGGUGCUUCAAAGCCAACAGACCAGCUCCUCUUCCUCCGGAUCCUCUUUUGAUCUGCCCAGGAAAGGGAUGCAUUGACACUCUCCUGCAUGCACCUGGCGAGAAGCCACCUGAAAGUCACUGUGGUUAAAGAUAUUGGUGGAGGUACCCCAGGAGCACUGUUACAAAUCCUUCUUGUUUUGGCAUCUCGUACAACAUUAUUAAGACACAGCUGAGAGUUGAUGGGUGUGUAAUGCAUAUGCCAAGGAAAUGUCACUAAUCCCAAAGCAAUCAAAAAGGAGACCUCAAACCAGAUGUUAAUUUGUUCUUUGUGUAACAAUGUAACCAAAAUAUUGAUGAUAAAAGUCAUAAUUUAAGAUUCAGAAUAAAUGGGUUUGAUGUCUGG